CUUUUCCGGGUCUCGAGGCUGCUGAAACCGAAACCGCUGUGCUGUGGGCGCAGCGCCGAGAUUGAUUCACCUUCACCUGUGCUGCACUCCAGCUGACCCAAGUAGGAAGCCAGACGAGCUGUAAAACAUGAACGGAAGAGUGGAUUAUUUGGUCACUGAGGAAGAGAUCAAUCUUACCAGAGGGCCCUCAGGGCUGGGCUUCAACAUCGUCGGUGGGACAGAUCAGCAGUAUGUCUCCAACGACAGUGGCAUCUACGUCAGCCGCAUCAAAGAAAAUGGGGCUGCGGCCCUGGAUGGGCGGCUCCAGGAGGGUGAUAAGAUCCUUUCGGUAAAUGGCCAAGACCUAAAGAACCUGCUGCACCAGGAUGCUGUAGACCUCUUUCGUAAUGCAGGCUAUGCUGUGUCUCUGAGAGUGCAGCACAGGUUACAGGUGCAGAAUGGACCUAUAGGACAUCGAGGUGAAGGGGACCCAAGUGGUAUUCCCAUAUUUAUGGUGCUGGUGCCAGUGUUUGCCCUCACCAUGAUGGAUCCUGAGCUUGAAAAAAAACUGAAAGAGAAUAAAAUAUCUUUAGAGUCGGAAUAUGAGAAAAUCAAAGACUCCAAGUUUGAUGACUGGAAGAAUAUUCGAGGACCCAGGCCUUGGGAAGAUCCUGACCUCCUCCAAGGAAGAAAUCCAGAAAGCCUUAAGACUAAGACAACUUGACUCUGCUGAUUCUUUUUUCCUUUUUUUUUUUUUUAAAUAAAAAUAUUAUUAACUGGACUUCCUAAUAUAUACUUCUAUCAAGUGGAAAGGAAAUUCCAGGCCCAUGGAAACUUGGAUAUGGGUAAUUUGAUGACAAAUAAUCUUCACUAAAGGUCAUGUACAGGUUUUUAUACUUCCCAGCUAUUCCAUCUGUGGAUGAAAGUAACAAUGUUGGCCACGUAUAUUUUACACCUCGAAAUAAAAAAUGUGAAUACUGCUCCAAAAACAGAGUCACGUAUUCCACUCUCCAACUACCCACAUAUUCCUUUUGCAAUAGCCAUUAGGGCAUCAUUUUGAUAUUUCAUUCUGAUUUCUGAUUCUCUGAUUUCUGAUUCCUAAUGAGGACAGUAGGUCUGGAUCCAAAUUCUCACAGUAAAAUCAAGCAGUAAUUUUCUCUCAUAUCUAUUAGGGAAAGAAAAAUGAUCACAGUCUGCUAAGAGUCUUGAUUUUCUUUGUAAUGCCUCACAUAGUAUGAUAAUCAGUCUCCAAAGCAUCACAUGAUAAUUACAAUGAUACCAUUAACAUGUCAAGGAAAUUAUAUUAUUUAUGGUUGUCAAAAAUUAUGAAGUAGUGUAUGAUUAUAAGCAGAUAUGGCAAAUUUGUUCAGUAAAUCCAUAGAUGACUACAUUUUGAGAAAUACUAAGAUAAUACUAAAAAUUAUGCCUUAGCAUAAUUUGCAUGCAAAAUUGCCCUCUAGUGUUUUUGUUUUGUUUUGAGACAUAGUCUCGCUCUGUUCGCCCAGGCUGGAGUGCAGGGGCACGAUCUCUGCUCACUGCAAGCUCUGCUUCCCGGGUUCACACCAUUCUCCUGCCUCAGCAUCCUGAGUAGCUGGGACUACAGGCACAUGCUGUCACACCCGGCUAAUUUUUUGUAUUUAGUAGAGAUGGGGUUUCACCACGUUAGCCAGGAUGGUCUCCAUCUCCUGACCUUGUGAUCCGCCCACCUCGGCCUCACAAAUUGCUGGGAUUACAGGUGUGAGCCACCACGCCUGGCCGAAAGUUAGUUGUUUUGAACUCAUUUUCUCCUUUUUACCCCUGCCUUUAUCAGCUUCUACCUUCUGGUUUCAUGCUGAGUUCUAGUUGCCUAAAGUCUCCAUUGAAACACUCCUGUUAUAAUUGCCAUAAAAUCAUAAAUCCACUCCCCCUUUCUCCUCCUAGUCAAAAUUUGUAUUCUUUUCAGCAGGUUGGUUUUAAUAAAAAGUAAAUUAAGUUGA